GAGGUGUGAGCAGCUGCCGAAGUCAGUUCCUUGUGGAGCCGGAGCUGGGCGCGGAUUCGCCGAGGCACCGAGGCACUCAGAGGAGGCGCCAUGUCAGAACCGGCUGGGGAUGUCCGUCAGAACCCAUGCGGCAGCAAGGCCUGCCGCCGCCUCUUCGGCCCAGUGGACAGCGAGCAGCUGAGCCGCGACUGUGAUGCGCUAAUGGCGGGCUGCAUCCAGGAGGCCCGUGAGCGAUGGAACUUCGACUUUGUCACCGAGACACCACUGGAGGGUGACUUCGCCUGGGAGCGUGUGCGGGGCCUUGGCCUGCCCAAGCUCUACCUUCCCACGGGGCCCCGGCGAGGCCGGGAUGAGUUGGGAGGAGGCAGGCGGCCUGGCACCUCACCUGCUCUGCUGCAGGGGACAGCAGAGGAAGACCAUGUGGACCUGUCACUGUCUUGUACCCUUGUGCCUCGCUCAGGGGAGCAGGCUGAAGGGUCCCCAGGUGGACCUGGAGACUCUCAGGGUCGAAAACGGCGGCAGACCAGCAUGACAGUCUGUUUAAACAAGCACACAGAGCUAGUAGUGGUUCCUCUGCUGGGCAGCUUGACUUAGAGCAGACCCAUGGGUGCGGGUGCGGUGAUGGAUAAAAUCACAUCUGUGAAGCAUGGUGGGACACUCCAUAAUACCCCUCAAGAGACAGAGUGGACGUUCCCCGAGUUCUUCCUGUUCUCAGCAGUCGGCCCCAUUGGCCCCAGGGAAGGGUGUCCUGGCCCCCCACUGUCUUCCUCAGUUGGGCAGCUCCGCCGCGUCCUCUUCUUCUUGGCCUGGCUGACUUCUGCUGUCUCUCCUCAGAUUUCUACCACUCCAAACGCCGGCUGAUCUUCUCCAAGAGGAAGCCCUAAUCCGCCCACAGGAAGCCUGCAGUCCUGGAAGCGCGAGGGCCUCAAAGGCCCGCUCUACAUCUUCUGCCUUAGUCUCAGUUUGUGUGUCUUAAUUAUUAUUUGUGUUUUAAUUUAAACACCUCCUCAUGUACAUACCCUGGCCGCCCCCUGCCCCCCAGCCUCUGGCAUUAGAAUUAUUUAAACAAAAACUAGGCGGUUGAAUGAGAGGUUCCUAAGAGUGCUGGGCAUUUUUAUUUUAUGAAAUACUAUUUAAAGCCUCCUCAUCCCGUGUUCUCCUUUUCCUCUCUCCCGGAGGUUGGGUGGGCCGGCUUCAUGCCAGCUACUUCCUCCUCCCCACUUGUCCGCUGGGUGGUACCCUCUGGAGGGGUGUGGCUCCUUCCCAUCGCUGUCACAGGCGGUUAUGAAAUUCACCCCCUUUCCUGGACACUCAGACCUGAAUUCUUUUUCAUUUGAGAAGUAAACAGAUGGCACUUUGAAGGGGCCUCACCGAGUGGGGGCAUCAUCAAAAACUUUGGAGUCCCCUCACCUCCUCUAAGGUUGGGCAGGGUGACCCUGAAGUGAGCACAGCCUAGGGCUGAGCUGGGGACCUGGUACCCUCCUGGCUCUUGAUACCCCCCUCUGUCUUGUGAAGGCAGGGGGAAGGUGGGGUCCUGGAGCAGACCACCCCGCCUGCCCUCAUGGCCCCUCUGACCUGCACUGGGGAGCCCGUCUCAGUGUUGAGCCUUUUCCCUCUUUGGCUCCCCUGUACCUUUUGAGGAGCCCCAGCUACCCUUUUUCUCCAGCUGGGCUCUGCAAUUCCCCUCUGCUGCUGUCCCUCCCCCUUGUCCUUUCCCUUCAGUACCCUCUCAGCUCCAGGUGGCUCUGAGGUGCCUGUCCCACCCCCACCCCCAGCUCAAUGGACUGGAAGGGGAAGGGACACACAAGAAGAAGGGCACCCUAGUUCUACCUCAGGCAGCUCAAGCAGCGACCGCCCCCUCCUCUAGCUGUGGGGGUGAGGGUCCCAUGUGGUGGCACAGGCCCCCUUGAGUGGGGUUAUCUCUGUGUUAGGGGUAUAUGAUGGGGGAGUAGAUCUUUCUAGGAGGGAGACACUGGCCCCUCAAAUCGUCCAGCGACCUUCCUCAUCCACCCCAUCCCUCCCCAGUUCAUUGCACUUUGAUUAGCAGCGGAACAAGGAGUCAGACAUUUUAAGAUGGUGGCAGUAGAGGCUAUGGACAGGGCAUGCCACGUGGGCUCAUAUGGGGCUGGGAGUAGUUGUCUUUCCUGGCACUAACGUUGAGCCCCUGGAGGCACUGAAGUGCUUAGUGUACUUGGAGUAUUGGGGUCUGACCCCAAACACCUUCCAGCUCCUGUAACAUACUGGCCUGGACUGUUUUCUCUCGGCUCCCCAUGUGUCCUGGUUCCCGUUUCUCCACCUAGACUGUAAACCUCUCGAGGGCAGGGACCACACCCUGUACUGUUCUGUGUCUUUCACAGCUCCUCCCACAAUGCUGAAUAUACAGCAGGUGCUCAAUAAAUGAUUCUUAGUGACUUUA